AGAGGGGCCCGAGCCACCCGGUCCGCCGCGUCCCCGCCGCCGCCGCCGCGUCCCCCGCCGGGGCCGACCGAGCCGAGCCGGGCCGGAGCGGCGGGCGCGGCCGGGCCGCCAUGGACCACAAGCCGCUGCUGCAGGAGCGGCCGCCCGCCUACAACCUGGAGGCCGGCCAGGGCGACUACGCGUGCGGCCCGCACGGCUACGGCGCCAUCCCCGCCGCGCCCCCGCCGCCGCCCUACCCCUACCUCGUCACAGGGAUACCCACCCACCAUCCCAGGGUCUACAACAUCCACAGCCGGACCGUCACCCGCUAUCCUGCCAACUCUAUCGUGGUCGUAGGAGGCUGUCCUGUCUGCAGCAACUUCGUGUACGACGACGGGAACCAACCCCUCCUACCGGCAAAGAGGGAGAAAAGACCCUAUCAGCAGUAGACAUGUGGACGGCAACCUCCCUGAACAACCUGGUGAGAGCUCAGGGCAGACAGGUCCACUGCUCCAGAAACGCCCAUGUGUGGAGGAAAUGAAAUUAAGGCUUUUAAUAGGUAAAUAUGGACUUUCACAUACACUGAACAAUGUGUAUUGUUAACAAUUUUUUUUUAAUAGAGACAGGGUCUCGCUCUGUUGCCCAGGCUGGAGUGCAGUGGUGCGAUCAUAGCUCACAGCAGCCUCGAACUCAUGGGCUCAAGCAAUCCCCCUGCCUCAGCAUCCGAGUAGCUGUGACUAGAAGUGUGCACCACCAUGCCUAGCUAAAAAGCAAUAUAUGUUGUAUGUAUAACAUUAAUUUGAUUUGGAUUACCCCUUUUUUUUUCCAUAUUGGUUUUAUUUAAUACAUCUGAACAAUCUGUCUAGAAAACUGACAAGCUAGUUACAGGAAGGCUUGUGCACAUAAUUAUGGCUGAAAUUAAGAGGAUUGCAUUCAAACUACCUACGUGCUAAACCUUAACAAAGUAUAUCUGAUAUGCAGAUUAUCUUCAAUAAAUCAAAUGCUAAUUUUAUUUAUUUUUUUGAGACAGAGUCUUGCUCUGUCACCCAAGGCUGGAGUGCAAUGGCGAGAUCUCGGCUCACUGCAACCUGCGCCUCCCAGGUUCAAUCCUGCCUCAGCCUCCCGAGUAGCUGGGAUUACAGGCGCCUGCCACCACGCCUGGCUAAUUUUUGUAUUUUUCGUAGAGAUGGGGUUUCACCAUGUUGGCCAGGCUGGUCUGGAACUCCUAACCUCAGGUGAUCUGCCCGCCUUAGCCUCCCAAAGUGCUGGGAUUACAAGCAUGAGCCACUGCACUGGCCAAAUGCUAAAUUUUUUUUAAAAACAAAAGAAUGUUUAAACUACUUUCAGACAGGUGACUUCAUACGCUCUAAUAACUAUGCAUGCACCAAAUGUAUCUCUACAUGCACAGACAUACAGAAAAUAGCCUGGGAUCGAAUAACUUCAGUUAACUAAACUAGAACUAAACCAUAAACUUAACUUUGGCUAAAAUGUGAGCAUGUCCACGAAGACAGUUUGCAGCUUGGCUGCUCUGGAAGGGAGGGGCCGUCUGGUGCCCUGCGGGGACCAUCACGCCCAGACUUACGCCUUGGACACGUCGUGUUCUCCAUAGAGCCAGCCAUCCUUCUCCUCGGGGAUGAGCAGCGUGAUGACAUCUCCCUGUGCAAAGCUGAGUAAGGUCUUGUUGGAGCCCGCAGUGUGCGGGAAGAUGGUCUUCACUUUCUGCUUCUUCAUCAUGUUCAGUCCCGUUGCAACCGAAACUGAUCGCUGUAAACUGGGAUCUUCGGAAGUACCUGUUGGAGGGAGUGUAGCAGUAAUGGCUUUUCAAAGCAUGAGAAUCAAUAGGCACAUUCCAAUGAGCAAACCCCAGGAAUCCACCUGUUCUCAUCUUGCCAACAAUGCUCCUUCCACGGAAACUGACCCUGUCCUAUUUCCUCGCUUUGAUCAUUGCCCAGAAGGAACAGGGACUGUUGAGAAACAGAGGCAGCGUGCAGCCUGAAGGCAUGCACCGUGCAGAAGAGGAUCCCUGCGGCUGCGGGCUCUUUUCCAGGCCCAAGGACAAGGCGGUGUGUGCCGGGUUGAUCUGCACUGCUUUAGCCAGGAUGGCUCUUCUUAGAGAGACAAACCGCUCCAACGCCAAACUGCCCUCGCAAUUCCAAUCGCAAAGGCAGGCUAGGGCCACAGUUCAAACCCAACUGCCAAUGUCCACAAAGAAAAGAAGAAAGCUGGAAAUGCAGUUGGUCUUGCCAUGCUGGCCGCUCAGCUUCUCACCCCCAGGCCUAAGAAGGACAAGGUGAGGAUGAGUUCCAUUUACAGAGUCCUCACCAGGUGCCAGUCACGAUCUCAAUGUCUCACAGCUGCCAUCCCGCCAGGCUCCCAGGAGGAAGGUGCUGCUAUUUAUUAUCCACAGGACAGACCCCACAGCUGGCAAGUGGCUGGGCCAGGAACCAGCUAGGGCAGGUUUGUCCCAUACUCUCUACCCAUGAGCACGAGGCUGUGCUGUUCAUGUCUCCAUUCAAACACAGGCUGAUAUUUCCACUCCAGGGGAAAAAAGGUAGAAAAAAAUAUAUAUAUAUGUAUGUAUAUACAUUUGAGACAGAGUCUCACUCUGUUGCCCAGGCUGGAGUGCAGUGGCAGGAUCACAGCUCACUGUAGUCUGGACUUCCCAGGCUUAAAGGAUCCUCCCUCCUCAGCCUCCUAAGUAGCUGGGACUACAGGCACACGCCGCCAUGCCAGGUUCAUUUUUAAAUUUUUUUGUAGAGACAGUGUCUCGCUAUGUUGCCCAGCCUGGUCUUGACCUCCUGGCCUCAAGUGAUCCUCCCAGCUUGGCCUCCCAAAGUGCUGGGAUUACAGGUUUGAGCCACUGCUUCUGGCCGUUUUUUUUUUCCAUUCAAAUUUUCCCAGGCUAGUAAUACAACAAGCAUCUUUAAUUUAAAACAAUGCAAGAUCUCUUUCUGCUUUAUUCUUGCAGAUUCUUCAUGAUUACAACAUAAACCUGCGCCCCCUUAACCUGCCACUCUCUACUUCGCUGGUGUUGAACCCACCAGCAGUUUUCUUUCUUUUUUGAGACAGAGUCUCGCUCUGUCGCCCAGGCUGGAGUGCAGUGGUGUGAUCUCGGCUCACUGCAACCUCUACCUCCUGGCUGGGUUCAAGCAAUUCUCUUGCCUCAGCCUCCUGAACAGCUGGAAUUACAGGCGCGUGCCACCAUGCUCGGCUAAUUUUUGUAUUUUUAGUAGAGACAGGGUUUCACCAUAUUGGCCAGGCUGGUCUCGAACUCCUGACAUCGAGAUCCACCUACCUUGGCCUCCCAAAGUGCUGGGAUUACAGGCAUGAGUCACCGCGCCCAAUCCUCCACCAGCAAUUUUCAUUCUGCUUUUACCAAUAAGAACCAGAGUCAUCUGAAUCACUGGGAUGCACAGAGUAUUACAUACUUUAACUGUGUAUUUUAGUUAACUGACAGGACUUCCUUCAAAGGCAAAUGCCUGCAGACCAUCAUCUUCCUCUACUGGGCCAUCCUAGUCAUCAUUCUGGAAAACUCUGUUCUUUUGCCCAAUAGCUUCACACGCUGUGGUCCAGGGCUCUCUCUCACAAACAGCUUGACUGCCGCAACCUUCACACCAUGGGGGCCUGUGAGACACCCCACGUGGAUGGGUUGGGGCCAUGGCACAGGUCUCGAGGGUCCUGGGUGCUAAAGACUGUGCAGAAGGACGGGGUCUGACCAGUGAAGCAGCCGGCAACAUCUGCAGACAGUCACUGGCUCCAACUUUUGUUUUUGUCACUGUGUCACCCAGGCUGGAGUGCAGUGGUGCGACCUCAGCUCAUUGCAACCUCCGCCUCCUGGGUUCAAGUGAUUCUCCUGCCUCAGCCUCCCGAGUAGCUGGGAUUACAGGCAGGCACCACCACGCCUGGCUAAUUUUUUGUAUUUUUAGUAGCGAUGGGGUUUCAUCAUGUUGGCCAGGCUGGUCUCAAACAACUGACCUCAGGUGAUCCACCUGCCUCGGCCUCCCAAAGGGCUGGGAUUACAGGCGUGAGCCACCGCGCCUGGCCUCCAUUUAUUUGUAAAUAGAUAAUUCUCAACAGUAUGUUUACUCUGGAUAAACAUCAGUCAGUGCGUAGAACUGGUAAAUGUCAGAGAAAUGUAUCACUUAUCAGAGCGUCUCACAGUCUAGUCCUGUAUUUCUUCUGAACUCACGCUCUGCAAAGCCAGGGCUGAAUGUAUCUACCAUACCUGCUUGUUUACCUCCAAACCUUGCAAUACAUUUAUACAAAAUAUUUAUUUCACAGCUUAUCUUAAAACAAAUGUAAAAGGUAUCUUCAAAUAAAUCAGACUGAAUCUCUUA